GCACAGUCCUCGGUCCCUGGUUCCCGCCAGGGAUGGCGGCGCGGACUCUGGCGAGCGCCUUGGUCCUCACGCUCUGGGUUUGGGCGCUGGCUCCGGCGGGGGCCGUGGACGCUAUGGGCCCUCACGCAGCCGUCCGUCUGGCCGAGCUGCUGACCCCGGAGGAGUGCGGCCAUUUCCGGUCGCUCCUGGAGGCGCCCGAGCCCGACGUGGAGGCCGAGUUGUCCCGGCUUUCUGAAGACCGGCUGGCGCGGCCUGAGCCGCUCAACACCACGUCGGGGUCUCCGAGCCGGCGGCGGCGGCGAGAGGCGGCCGAGGACCCGGCGGGCAGGGUAGCCGGGCCUGGAGAGGUGUCCGACGGCUGCCGGGAGGCGCUGGCGGCCUGGCUGGCCCCCCAGGCCGCGUCCCUGUCCUGGGACCGCCUGGCUCGGGCCCUGCGGCGCAGCGGCCGCCCGGACGUGGCCAGGGAGCUGGGCAAGAACCUCCACCAGCAGGCGACGCUGCAGCUGCGCAAGUUCGGGCAGCGCUUCCUGCCGCGGCCCGGCGCCGCCGCCCGCGUGCCCUUUGCCCCGGCCCCGCGCCCCCGGCGCGCCGCGGUCCCCGCGCCGGACUGGGACGCCCUGCAGCUGAUCGUGGAGCGCCUGCCGCAGCCCCUGUACGAGCGGAGCCCCAUGGGUUGGGCGGGGCCGCUGGCGCUCGGCCUCCUCACCGGCUUCGUGGGGGCGCUGGGCACCGGGGCGCUGGUCGUCCUGCUCACGCUAUGGAUCACUGGCGGCGACGGCGACCGGGCGUCGCCCGGCAGCCCCGGCCCGCUCGCCACAGUGCAGGGCUGGUGGGAAACAAAGCUGCUCCUUCCUAAAGAGCGGCGCGCGCCCCCGGGGGCCUGGGCUGCAGAUGGGCCAGAUUCUCCCUCACCUCACAGUGCCCUUGCCCUCAGCUGUAAAAUGGGAGCACAGUCUUGGGGCAGUGGUGCUUUGGACGGUUUAUAAACGUUAAGAAAUACCGAAA